AUGAGGUAAAUGUUGCUGUUGCGUCUUCCCCCUCACCGCAGUCACGCCAGCCCGUUAGAUUGCAAGUUGCAGGACCGCUGUAGGAAAUGUUAUUCGCCGCGGUCAGGACAGGCCUGUCCGCCCGCCCUCGCCGCAGCCUGGCUUCGUCGUUGCGAGCGCCGGGGAGGCCGUCCCCGGGGAGGGCGGAGGAAGGAGCUGACUUUGGGUUUGCGUCCCGCUCGCUGCUCUGCCCCGGGGCCAGCCAAGGACGACGCUUGGAGGCCUCAGGCCGGGAGAUCAUCUUCAGACACCAACGAAAGUGAAAUAAAGUCAAAUGAAGAGCCACUCCUAAGAAAGAGUUCUCGCCGGUUUGUCAUCUUUCCAAUCCAGUACCCUGAUAUUUGGAAAAUGUAUAAACAGGCACAGGCUUCCUUCUGGACAGCAGAAGAGGUCGACUUAUCAAAGGAUCUCCCUCACUGGAACAAGCUUAAAGCAGAUGAGAAGUACUUCAUCUCUCACAUCUUAGCCUUUUUUGCAGCCAGUGAUGGAAUUGUAAAUGAAAAUUUGGUGGAGCGCUUUAGUCAGGAGGUGCAGGUUCCAGAGGCUCGCUGUUUCUAUGGCUUUCAAAUUCUCAUCGAGAAUGUUCACUCAGAGAUGUACAGUUUGCUGAUAGACACUUACAUCAGAGAUCCCAAGAAAAGGGAAUUUUUAUUUAAUGCAAUUGAAACCAUGCCCUAUGUUAAGAAAAAAGCAGAUUGGGCCUUGCGAUGGAUAGCAGAUAGAAAAUCUACUUUUGGGGAAAGAGUGGUGGCCUUUGCUGCUGUAGAAGGAGUUUUCUUCUCAGGAUCUUUUGCUGCUAUAUUCUGGCUAAAGAAGAGAGGUCUUAUGCCAGGACUCACUUUUUCCAAUGAACUCAUCAGCAGAGAUGAAGGACUUCACUGUGACUUUGCUUGCCUGAUGUUCCAAUACUUAGUAAAUAAGCCUUCAGAAGAAAGGGUCAGGGAGAUCAUUGUUGAUGCUGUCAAAAUUGAGCAGGAGUUUUUAACAGAAGCCUUGCCAGUUGGCCUCAUUGGAAUGAAUUGCAUUUUGAUGAAACAGUACAUUGAGUUUGUAGCUGACAGAUUACUUGUGGAACUUGGAUUCUCAAAGGUUUUUCAGGCAGAAAAUCCUUUUGAUUUUAUGGAAAACAUUUCUUUAGAAGGAAAAACAAAUUUCUUUGAGAAACGAGUUUCAGAGUAUCAGCGUUUUGCAGUUAUGGCAGAAACCACAGAUAACGUCUUCACCUUGGAUGCAGAUUUUUAAAAAACCUCUCGUUUUAAAACUCUAUAAACUUGUCAUUGGUAAAUAGUAGUCUAUUUUCCUCUGCUUAAAAAAAAUUUUAAGUAUAUCCUUUAAAGGACUGGGGGUUUGCUCAAAAGGAAAUCCAAAACCUAUUCUAAACAAUUUGCAUUUAUAUAAUUUUCCUGUUUAACAACAAGAGUGUGACCUAAAUGCUUUUGUCUUGUCACUGAAAUAAAAGAUGGCAUUAUGUGGUUAAGAGCAUGGGGCGAGGGGUCAGACAUGAGUCUAAGGUUCUGCCCUUACUCCAGUGUGUGACCCUUGGCAAGUCAGUUAAUCUUGGUAAACCUCGGUGUACUUAUCUUUAAAAUGGGAGUAAUAGUAGGUCCUAAAUUCAUAGAGUGGAUAUUAGGAUUAGGAUGCAAAAAUAAAUGCUUAACCAACACUACUACUGUUAGCACCACUACUAAUUAUCAUUCAUUGAUAAUAUUAAUUGCAAUGAUGUUGUAAUAAAAUACUCUCAUUUCCUUAAAAUAAUUGUGAUUCUAGGUCCUAGGAUCUAGAAUUAGAUCUUUGUAUUUUUAAUGCUUAGGGGAAGAAUAUAAGUAUCUCCUUAAAAAGAACAUAAUUCUCAUUCACGCAAGAAUAAGUUCUUUGAAUUCCUUAGUAUGUAGUGAAGAAAAUUUAGUUGUUAGUUGCUUUGGGAAGCCUACUUAUGGAGUGGAAACCAGGAGGUUAUCAUGGUAGUUGACCUUAUAAGAAAAAUGAUUCUUCUUCAGAAAUUAAAAACAUAACUAUUGCCAGAUUUAGCUCUGGAAUGUUUAGAAUCAGGCUAGAAUAGCAUUUUCCAAAGAAUAUUCUAAGAGCUAUUAGCUCCUCUAGAUAUUUUUUUGGGGGAAAAAGGGGAUUCUGUGGUCAGAUGAGUUUGGGAAAUGCUGAACACUUCAUUCUUCUUUAGCAAGUACAGUCAGUACAUCAAAGACUGAGCAGUUCAGUGGUACAUAAAUUUAUCUCGCCCUGCAUAUUCCCAACAUACUUAACACAGAUGUUUUUUACCUGUUAACAUCUCACCCAGCUAGUGUUCCUCAGAACAAAGAUUGGAAAAAGCUGGCCGAGAACCAUUUAUACAUAGAGGAAGGGCUUAUGGACUGAGAAAGGGAGAACAUGGUAGGGAUUAUUGAAUCAUUUCAAAUUUAUACCAGCCUGAAUAGUGUACCAGCAAUUGACUUAGGCUGUGUUUCUUUAUGGUUUUAAAACUCUUGAGCUGUUAUAAGAGAUAGUUCUUUUAAUGUGACUAUGCAACAUGAUAGCCAAUGGUGAGGGAAAAGGAGGUUUCUCUAGAAGAGUCUGAUGAAAGGCCGGGAACCAAGGUUUUUGAGAAGUCUGCCCCUAUUUAUUUUUAGUAAGUAUCAAGAGGUAGCCUGAGCCUAGUUAGAGUUAGACCUGUCUUUGGAUGAAGAAGUCUUAAUACUGAAAUACUGAAUUUUUAAUACAUUAUUAUUUGGUAUUCUGUAUACCCCUUCAAGCAGUUGUUUCCCAUUCCCAACAAACUGUACUUUAUACAAUUCUGGAUGCUAAAACUUAGAGAUUUUCUCUUUGCAUAAAUUUUGGCUCCAUUCUUUCCAUAACAAUCUAAUCAAAACUGGGAGUUCUCAAGUGAAUGCAAAAGGAGCAGGCCAUAACUUUAUUUGUUAGAUACACUGUCAGAAACUUGAGAUCUUUUGGCCUAUGAUAAUACCAUUAAUUUUUGCAUUGCUUCAGUUUGCCAAGUGUUUUUACAUCAUCUCAUUUGAUCUCAAAACAGCUUGACAGAGCAACUGUUAUUGAAAUAUUACAGAUGGAAAGAAUGAGGCUCAGGGAAGUUAAAUGACUUGGCCAAGAUCUGCUCAUCGUCACUGUCUGUACAGUAUUUUUUUUUAGAGGUUGUAAUGUCUCAGAUUUAGUCCUUUACCAUCUAUGUUGAUUUGCUUUUGUCUAUUUCCUCAUUAAUUGAAUAUACUUUAAAUAUAUAUAUUAAAGUAUCAAAAUAUAGAGAGACAUUUGAACUGUAUUCAGGUAAUAUGUUUAAAGAUAUUUAUAUAUUGCCAUACAAAAACUUAACAUUUAAAACUGAUAAUAUCUGUAAUGACAUCAGAAUGAAAGAAAAAAAAUUGUACAGUGUAUAUUCCUUUGUUUUGAAUCCAAAUCUUUUUCAUAGGUAAUGACAGAUGCCUUAAUGUGAAGCUUAUUUAUAAUAGCAAUAAACCUAACUGGAUUUGGAUGAAGAAGUCUUAAUACUGACAUACUGGAUUUUUAAUGCACUGGUUUGUUAUUUGGUAUUCUAUCUCUUUUUCCAGGCCUCCAGGUUGCACAUUUAUUUAUUAUGUUCAAUACUUUGGUUCUUAGUUCUUAAAGAAUCAAGAAGUUGUGUAAUCUUUUAAAAAUAUUAUCUUGCAGAUAAAGAAAAAAAUUAAGAGUGUGUUUACAACUGUUUUCUCUUUUUUACAGUACAUGUAUUUAAAUCAUUGCUAUAAUAAAGUUAAGUUCAUUAGGAAUAUAAAAACUUGCAGUUCUAUGAUAGAUUGCAUUUAUUAAAAAUGUUUCAUUGUAUCACAUAGAAAUAUGGCCAGGAAGGACUUGAGAAGACAGUUUGAUCCAUUGCUUUUAGACAGGACUGGGUUUUGCUGUCCAAUUAUAUACAAUAAUAGUUUUUCUUACAACUAAGCUGGCCCCAGCCUUGUCUUGAUAUUAAUACAUGAAAUUUUUAUAAUUGUCUCAUUGUCUCAUUUAGAAACAUCCAUAUUUUUCUGCUUUUUCUAUUGCCAUUUUUUAUUUGUGCAUGAAUUGAUUAUUGAGAAAAUGUAGCAGUUUGCAUAUUUAAAAAUUAAUCAUUUUGCAUUUUACAUUUAAAUAUGCUAACAUCACUGUCAUAGAAUUCCCAAAUUUCAUUUGUAGAUACUGAACUAAGGGCUAAUGUCAGGAGCUGAUUUUUAAUGAUAAAGCUGCAGAUGGGCUAAAUAAAAGCCAAAUUAAUCCUACAAUCAGGUAUUAUGUUUUUAAACCAAGUUGAGUGAAUUGGUAGUGGACUUGGGAAAUCUUCCCCAGCAGAAUCUGGAUGAAUGGCACAGAAUUGAAAUCUCUUUGUUUCCCACCAUUUCCCUUUAAGUGCUCUGCUCCUUUGUAAAAAGUUAAAGAUUUGAAAGAGAAUCUCAUAUUCCCGAGGCAUUAGGAAGAAAGGAUUUAAUCCCUUCAAUUUGGGGCUUAAUCUUGUUUAAAAAAAUGUAAGUGAAGAUGGAAGGCUGGAGAGAAUGAUUGCUUUUUGUACAGUUAAAUAAGGUCACAAUAUUCUUACAUACUUUGUUUUACAACUGUGUUUUCAUUUUUUCAAAUGUCUGGCCAUUUAGCAAAGUUAUUUACUAUUUACUGUGUACAUAGAAAGCUUUAUUAUGUGUGGUGUAUCUAAAUUUUUUUUGCUGAAAUACAUUAUGGUCAAUCAAGCCAAGCCUGCAUGUACAGAAUUUGUUUUUUUUUCAAAUAAAUUAGUUGUUUUCUUAUUUUUUUGGCUUAGUAUGUUGAAAUAAACUAUGGUAUCUUCAUCAUUUUGUACAUUUCCUUUUUGAGGAAGGUUUCUUUAUAAGUGCAAGGGCUACCCUAAUAAAGGAAUGUAUAUACUUACU